AAAGCCUUCUAAAUAUUUUCAUGAAGGUGCAAUAGAUCUCCAGGGCACAUGUUGCUAAACAUGAAUCAUUUGCUUCAUUGAUAAUUAUAUUUUAAGAUAAAUGUUAUUGUAUUUAGGGUUUACAACGUAUUACGGGAUAUGUAUAGACAGGAAACGGGUUACUAUAGUGAAGCAAGUUAACAUAUCCAUCAUGUUACAGUUACUUUUUUGUGUGACAAGAGGAGCUAAAAAUAUACUUAUUUAACAACAGUUCCUAAUGCACUACAAUGUUAUUAACUACAAUCCUCAUGUUACUCUAGCCUUGCUGACCCCCCCUCACCUGCUACUUUGUAUCCUUUGAACUCUACUUCCUCCUUUUCUCUCUCCCUUCCUUCCAUCCGUCCCAAACCCCUGGUAACCACUAUUUUCUUCUCUUAUCUCUGUUUUUUUAAUUCCGCAUGUAAGUGAGAUCAUGCAGUAUUUUUCUUUCUGUGUCUGACUUACUUUGCUUAGCAUAAUGUCCUCCAGGCCCGACCAUGUUGUGGGAAAUGGCAGGACCUCCUGAUUCCCUUUUUAGAGACAGUGCUCACUGUGGCCAGGCCUUUCUUAAUAUCGUGCUUCACACUGGAUAUGGUGCUGUGUUCUUUGCAAAAGGAUUUCACUUUUUUAGGUUAAAAAACAACCAUCAACAAGGGACAAGAUGUGUCCUAGCAGCCACUCAAGGAGAGAGGCUCCGAAUCAGUGGUCAGGAGAGUCAGCUCUGGGGUUGGCCACUGGUGGCCUGCACGGCUGAGGGCUGGUCCCUCCACACAGGGACACCGGGCCCACUUCUGAAAACCACAUUUCAGGGUGUCUUUGACAGUCAAGAAGUGGGGAGCAACUGAAGAUAUUUGGCCUGAAAUGGGGGACCUCUGGGGGGGACAAGAUCACUCUGCUCCAAUAUCUGAAGGCCAACUGCAUCCCUCGGAUGGCUUUAAUUUAAAAGAAUUCUUUUGAAAUAGAAAAUAACAAGUGUUGGUGAGCAUAUGGAGAGAUUGGAACACUCAUACAUGGCUGGUAGGAAUGUAAACUGGUGCAGCCGCUGUGGAAAACAGUUUGGUGGCUCCUCAAACCGUUAAAACAUAGAAUUACCAUAUGACCCAGCAGUUCCACUCCUUGGUCUAUACCCAAGAGAAAUGAAAACAUAUGUCCCUGCAGAAACUUAUGUUAACUUAUGAACAAUGUUCACAGCAGCGUUAUUCAUAAUAGCCAAAAUAUGGAAGCGACCCAAGCACCCAUCAGUGGAUGAAUGAAGAAAAUGUGGUACCAUAUGUAUAUAUAUAGGAAUAUUAUUCAGUCUUAAAGAGGAAGCAAAUUCUGAAAUAUGCCCGAAUGUGGAGGGACCUCGAAAGCAUUAUGCUAAAUGAAAGACGCCAUGGCAAAAGGUUGUAUAGUCCCUCUCUGUGAAUAUCCAGAAAAAGAAAAUCCCUUGAGACAGGGAAUUGGGGGAGGUGGGAGUGAGAGCAUAGCUCAGUGGGUACAGGCUGUUUCUCUGAGGAAAUAAGAAGGUUUUGAAUCCAGAGAAAGGUGGUAGUUGCACAACAUUAUGAAUGCAGUGAACACCACUGAAUUGUACAUUUUUAAAUGGUUAAUUCUAUGUUAUGUGAAUUUUACCUCAAUUUAAACAAUAAUCUGAGGGCUGUCAUUCUGUGUGACCCCUGGACAUAUGGCAAGAGGAAAUGAGUAGAAGCUCCAGGAGCACAGCAGGGAGGAGGGAGAGCAGUAUUUUUGCUCAGCAGGAAAAACUGACUCAUAAAUACAACUAGUAGGAAAUUGAAGAGGCCGCCCAAGAAAGCAGCAAGUGCAGGGGACUGUAGAGUGCCUGUCGGGUGCUGCACUCAACCCCGAGAGCAGCAGUUCUCACCCCGAGGACACGUGGGAUUCACUUGGUGGCACAAGAAAGCCACACUUGGGCCCCACCCCAGGGAUGCUGACGCUGUUGGCCUAAGGUGUGGACUGGGCAUCCGGACAAAGGCCCCUGGUGUCUUAGCUUUAGGUGGAAACAGAUGACCUUUUGUGUCCCUCCCAUCCUACCUCGGCCCCAACAGGGAUUUCUGUUUUAAUGACUGUGGUGCCUGCGAGCCUAGGAUCAUCACUGUUCAGUGUGAGUGGUGUACCCACAGCAUCCGCCUCACCUGGAAGCUGGCUGGGAAUGCAGCGUCUCCCCUCCCCACCCCCGCCCAGUCAGAAUCCAUACUUUAGCAAGAUCCCAGGGGACCUGUGUGCCCAUCUGAGUUUCAGAAGUGCUGCUGGGCCGGGGCAUGGGGGCUCACCCCUGUGCUCCCAGCACUUUGGGAGGCCAAGGCAGGCAGAUCACUUGAGGCCAGGAGUUUGAGACCAGGCUGGCCAACGUGGCGAAACCCCAUCUCUAGUAAAAAUACAAAAAUUAGUCAGGCGUGGUGGCAGGUGCCUGUAAUCCCAGCUACUCGGAAGGCUGAGGCAGGAGAAUCACUUGAACCCAGGAGGCGGAGGUUGCGGUGAGCUGAGAUCACAGCACUGCACUCCAGCCUGGGCCACAGAGUGAGACUUCAUCUCAAAAAAAAAAAAAGUGCUGCUGUCGAUCUUUAUUUACAAGACACUUCGAGGUGCUUUUCCUCAUUUUAUCUUCUGAACAAUCGCUGGUUUGUUCAGCUGUUUGACAGGGGAGGAAGUCCAGGCGCAGAGGGCUUCACUCACUCCACAUGCCACGGACAGUGCUGGUCUCCCACGUGCCCCAUUCAGGGCCUUCUCCCCCAGGUCCAGGGCCUGCUUCAGCUCUCUGUGACACCCACCACCUCCCUCAUGUGCUCGCAGUGCCCUGCCCGGAGCCCAGGCUGGGUAAUUAUUGGGUAUGCUGAAACUGCUGGGGCUGGGGAGACCCCGUGCCUCAGCUUGGAGCCUGAUGCCAUGGGAAUCCUCAAUGCAUGGCUCAGCUUGUCAUUAGCUUUUCCCUUUCUUUUUUCAUUCUUUGUUUUGAAAUAAUUAUAGAUUCAAAGGAAGUCACCAAGAGGUUCAAGUUCAGUGUACCCACCACCUGGUUUCCCCCAGUGGCAACAUCUUAACGUCACUAUAGCACAAUAUCACCCCCAGGAAGGCGGCACUGCCACAGGGGCCUGUAGAAUUGUGUCAUUUGCCACAUUUGUGGAUUUGCGUAACCACCACCCAUUUCUUUCCUUGACUUAAAACAAAAAAACAAACAGCCGGGCGCAGUGGCUCAUGCCUGUAAUCCCAGCACUUUGGGAGGCCAAGGUGGGCGGAUCACAAGGUCAGGAGUUCGAGACCAUCCUGGCUAACACAGUGAAACCCCAUCUCUACUAAAAAUACAAAAAAAAUUAGCCGGGCGUAGGUGGUGCAUGCCUGUAGUCCCAGCUACUCGGGAGGCUGAGGCAGGAGAAUGGCGUAAAACCCGGGAGGCGGAGGUUGCAGUGAGCCGAGAUCGCACCACUGCGCUCCAGCCUGGGAGACAGAGCGAGACUCCGUCUCAAAACAAACAAACAAACAAAAAACGAUGGGGUCCCCGAAAACACACUUUAUAAAGACUGAUUUCCUGCUGGCAGGAGAGAGAGCUGCUGUACAUCACAAAGCAAGGCGGCCCACUAGAGUGGUAUGGUCAGCGACCUCUGCCUUGCCUGGGUGAAGUGUCUCUCUCUCUGUCUCUGUCUCUCUCUCACACGCACACAUGCACGCACACACAUGCCAUGCACUUUCUCUGUGGAAGACUUCAAAGUGUUUGGUGGCUGUUCUGAGACCUGUUCCUCCUCGGCUGGGCUAGGGGAGGGGCCCACUCCUUUUACCUGUGUUUCUUUUUAGAGGAGAAACUGACACAAAGUCAGAUAGUCUUGGGGAUGGAAGUUGCUCUCAUCUGUAAGAAAAGGAAACUGACCUAACCAGCAGGUAAUCACUUGAAAUCACUUGUGUCCCGUGCUGGAAACAGCUCCACAGCAGUGUCUAUGAUGGAUUGGAACCUACACAGCUAGAGGAAGAAUUUGCAUCCAGAAACCACAGGAGCAGAUGACCCACAAGUGUAGCUAUUUUACUUCUUUCAUGUUAAAUUCCAAAUAAAAGGAUGAUUAUCUUUGAACUGACCCCAGUCCAAAGUACAAAUGCCUGGCUGAGAUCCACCAAGGCCAGAUGUUGUCAUCAGUGACUGGGUUUAUGCCAGGCUAUCGGUGAACUGGGUCAGAGAUGGUGCAGGCAAGGUUGCUGGGUCAGGGCAGGUUCACAGCCCAGUCAUUCCUAACCAAGAACAUCAGCACCUGACUGGAGGGUGGGAAUGAGGUUCCUGACCUGCUGACUCAUUUGCAGAGUGGUGUGUCAGAGCCACACACGGUAGCAGCAUAAACCUGAACUUCAGGUAACCACACGCCAUGGGAUGCUGCAGAUUUAUGUGCCCACUGCUUGCAGCUGAGAGGACCAGCAUGAAUGGCUCUAAUUUGUCACCAUGGCACAGUCACAGAUGGAGAAUGCUCUGUCAUAACCAGCGCUCCCAGUCUCCAUAGGUUCUUAGCACCCUUCCCCAUCCAUGUUUACCUGUACAGCCACCUGUGCAGGUCAUUCUUGCCCAGAAUAGUACAUGAGCUAAACAGCCAUCUUCAGGUGGUUAUAAAACCUCAUAUUUAUAUGAGGUUUCAUAGUUUACAAAAGUUACUUCUUAUUCCACCUAAUGAAGAAACCACAGUCCAGAAAAGUUUGGUGCCUCCCCCGAGGCCACCUACCUGGUCAGUGAUGGAUCAGCACCACAGUUCCCAUCUUCUCAUUACACCUCCCUACUGGUUAGGCCCCAGCCCACACAGAGAAGUGUUUCUGUUUCACCCCUGGAGAGGGCCCUGAAGCAUCUUGUGAGUUUGUGGAAAGAGAAGAGGAGCAGCUCUUGCUUCCGUGGGGAGCACAGCCAGACUCCUGUCUUCAUGUCCUGUCCCUUAAAUGCCCUCCAAAACCGGGGGCAGGUGCUCGAGAGAACUUGACCCUGAUUCCGGAUUAUGGGGUUUUCUAAACUCAGUACUGUGGCUGAGAUCUGUGGGGCAUUUUGCAAGCUGCUUGCUUUUGUGUGAAACCCCUAUAUUUGUCAGUAUUUUAAGUUUCUGUGAGGCUGUUCUUGAAUUCAGUUCCUUUCUCUUUGCCUAAAUGCAAGCCACACCCUCAUCUCCUCCCGUUGACCAUAUAAGAGGUCUCAAGGGCACUGAGGAACUUAGCAGAAAGCAAACAGUACCUUCAGAAGAUUAAAAAAAAAUUAUUGCAUUUGUUUUUCUACAACCAAGAUAAGAGACAGUAGAUAAAGGAAUGUGUAUGUCUUGUACAGCUCACUAGCCCCACCAUCUCUGAUACGGACCAGUUCUUCCUGCCCCUUGAAUAAGUAUCCCUUGUCUUAUCAUAGUUUACAUCCUGCUGUGAUGCCAUGUGACAUACAUGCUCUCGCACACACAUUAUUAAGACUUCACUCCUUGUGAUCAAGGCUGAGAAAGAUUGUGGUGGUGUUAUUGUUAAUAUAAGAUUUAUGACCUCAAAAUGUUUGCAAGCUUGGGGUCAGAGAUGGAGCAUUCCUCAGAGGGAGUCAGCCUGGGGUCCUUCUUACAUAGACAUGAACAUAGUUUCUCCAGAGCAAGGCAGAAUACACAGUUUAAACCAUGGGAAGGAGGAAAGACUCAAAGGAGUGAUUUAGUAAGAGUAUAGGUAAAGAAGGGAGAAAAUAUUAGUAUUUCUAGGAGAGUUAGAAGGACUUAGUACUUCUGCCGUUUUGUUUUAAAAUAUAUUUUUUUAAUAUAUAAAGAGACAUCUUGGCUCUCCCUAACGAAAAUGGCCUAAGAUCCUUUAUAUAUAUAUAUAAUUUUUUUUUUUUUGAGACGGAGUCUCACUCUUUCACCCAGGCUAGAGCGCAGUGGCACAGUCUUGGCUCACUGCAAGCUUCACCUUCUGGGUUCACGCCAUUCUCCUGCCUCAGCCUCCCGCGUAGCUGGGACUACAGGUGCCCACCAGCACGCCCAGCUAAUUUUUUUUGUAUUUUUAGUAGAGAUGGGGUUUCACCCUGUUAGCCAGGAUGGUCUCUGUCUCCUGACCUCAUGAUCCGCCUGCCUCGGCCUCCCAAAGUGCUGGGAUUACAGGCGUGAGCCACCGCGCCCAGCCGAUCCUUUGUAUUCUUAAUGAAAGAGGGAAUGAAUUGCAAUGAAUAUGUACUGCUUCUCCAGAAAACAGAAAAAUUUUUAAUGUUUUUAUUUAAACCAGACAUAUACUUUUUUAUUUAUUUCCUUGUUGGUUUCUUUUUCUUCCAAAUAGGUUGCAAAAAUGAAAUUUCUGUUUAAAUUUAUAACAUGCAAGAGUAUAUGUGUAUGUGGCCUUGGAAUGAUUAUUUAGUUUUGUUCCAAAGAUCUGAUAGUUUUUAAAUGAACUCUAUAAUUUAGGGUACUCUGGGAAUUGAAAACUUCGUGCUUUAUUUAGGUAAAGAUAUCCUGAAUUGCUUACUUAAGUAAGUCAAGUAAAUGGAACGUUCUUUGUGAUAAUGCUGUUGCAUUAUAAGAAAUGCUUUGAAUCAUAGGUAGGACUAAUGUAUAGCCUAUUUAUUUAUUUAUGAGAUGGAGUCUUGCUCUGUCACCCAGACUGGCAUGCAAUGGUGUGAUCUUAGCUCACUGCAACCUCCCCCAGCCAGGUUCAAGUGAUUCUUCUGCCUCAGCCUCCUGAGUAGCUGGGAUUACAGGCACCUGGCUAAUUUUUCUAUUUUUAGUAGAGACAGCCUAGCCAUGUUGGCCAGGCUGGCCUCAAACUCCCGACCUCAGGUGAUCUGCCUGCCUCAGCCUCCCAAAGUACUGGGAUUACAGGCAUGAGCCACCGAACCCGGCUAGCCAAUUUAUUUUAACAGCAUUUCACUUUCAAUUUUGUUAAAUUUGGCUAGACAUGUAAAAUCAUUUAUUUAAAAUUUAAAAAUCCAAACUUCUCCCUAUUUUGUCCAGAAUUUCAAAAUUGCAGUGAGUUGUGGUCGCCUGGAAACCAGGUGUAUGAUACUUUGUUAAGCACACUAAUUGGCAGCUUGGAGUUUUGCAUUGCAGAAGGCUCGUUAGUGAGGGUGGGUGGGAAUCCACACUCCUCCAAUUAGUGGGCCCCCAAGCCACUCGCACAUUUAAAGUAUGAUUCACUUUACCCAAGUUUGUUUGUCUUCAGCUCUUCAGGAAAACACUGUUACACAAGCCAAGGUCUCCUAUCCAGCAACCUUUUGGAUCCCGAGGUCUGCACAUAAAAGGACUUGCUCUGCAGGCUCCCUGGUAGCUGGUGAAUAUCUUGGGAAUUUAAAUAUGAAGAUAGUUGAUGUCCAUAGCUAGGAUCUGUUAUUUAAAUGUAGAAGCAUUUAAAUAUGCCUUUGGAGUUGUUUUUUUGCAUUGUGAUAGUAGCCACCACCUGAGCUAACAAUUCAUUGAGUUUUAUGCUGUCCCACAUUCUAGCUGCUUUAAGGGAUUGUGUUCUCAGGUCUCACAGAUGGCCUGUGAAGGGGAGAAACUGAGGCAGAGAGGGUUAGGAACUUGCCUAAGCUAGUUAAGCAACAGUCACGAUUAGAAGCCAGGAUCUUUCAGGACUGUUCCCACGUUAUGCGAGAGUCCUUGCCUCUCUUCAUAAAUGGUAGAUUUCCCAUCUCCUUUAAUAUCCUCUAGAUGAAUUCAUGAACAAAGGCCAAGGGACAGGAGAAAGAGAGAAAGGAGGAAGAAAUGAUGUCAGCUCUUUCCUUCAGUUCUUAAAAAUGCCAAAGACAAAACUUUCAGACAAGGUCGUUUCCUGGAAGAGGUGGGGUAAACAUUCCCAGAGUCAUGAGUUUUUAGAUUUGAAUGUUUCUAAAAUGUUGAUUGACAGAACCUUCUAAUACAUUUGUUAUAAACGUGACAUAAAGGGGAAAAAUGUCCAGCAUUUUGAGGAAGAAAGGGCUCUAAAUAUACAUAACUGCAUUUGAACAGAUUCCUUUGCUUCCUCGUUGGCCUGGGCUGCAAGGCCACUGUCCUCUUAUGAGCCCUAGGAAGCAGGACUGGCCUCCUGAGGACCCCAGCAUUAGCCUCCAGGUUUGUGCUGGGCCCUCCUGAGACAACCCCAAUCCAGACACUAGCUCCUAUAAGUAGAGCACCUGAGACUCAGGGGAAUUCCCUCAAAGCGUUCCAGCUUCUGAGCCAGAGAGGCCAGAAGUGGAAGCCUUUCUGUCGGACAGCUACAGCCCAGACUGGAUGCAGGAACAGCAGGAACAGAGCAGUGGCCUCCUCCGUGGCAUGGGGCCUUGUGCCCACCAAUCCUGGCACCACUGAACCACUGACUCAAGUCCGUCCUCAGCUCCAGUGAGCCUCUUGUUAUUGCCAGUGGCUGACGGAGAGGUGAGGGGAGAGGACGUCAUGCAGGCGAGCUGGGAGGUAGCACCACGGUUUCUCAGCAGUGUUCGUGCAAAUUAUCACUAUAAUGCACCCGUGCAGGCCCAGCAGCCUGUGCAAGUAUCACAGCACCAUACAGACAUGAAUUCAUGUGUCUUUAAUAACAGGGAAAUGGCAAUGUGUCAAUUUACACAGUUGUUUUUCUGCAGUUUUUUCUUUUUCUUUUUUUUUUUUUGAGCCAUCUUCCCAAGUGUUCUCUGGGUUUUCCUCUUACCCGGGUCCCCUGUCUGCCAUCCACAGGCUGGCAUGAGCCACCCAGGCUGGGUCUGGGAUCAGCCGAGGGCCUGGGCUGGUGCCGGCACCGCCCCUCUCCGCGAACGGGCCCUGCAUUCGCAUCAUUAGUUCAUCACCAUGGAAGAACUGGGCUGUCAAGCUGACCUACUUUUCUUGUUUGCCCACAGCAGGCUAAGCCUGUUUAGCCUCAUCCAGAGGGGCUGGGCAGAGCAAGUUGCUUUCCGAGUCAUACAGAUGGCAGUCUUCUGAGUGAGUGUGGUUGAAUCUGUUUGCCCUUUUUGCCCUUAGUCUGCAGAGUUAGGGCCCAGCACCCAGGAUGGCUUGAGUCCAGGUCCAAGCACAGGGGCAUCCUGCAACCCAUAUUCAGCCUCUCCCGAAGAGAUCCUGCAUUAGGAUGAAUUAUUGCGGGAACCAAUGCCAGGCUUCUUUCCAAACUUUAAACACAGAUUCCUAAAUGGAAGCUCUUCAUAUUCUAUACUAAGCCCUAAGAACAUCAGCCACUUGCAGAGAUGCCAGGAGGGUGGGACCCAUGCCUGUGCUUGAGGGGUUUACCAUCCAGUGGGGGAGGGUUGUGAACAGCUAAAGCCAAGGAGAAGCAGAAACAGAAGAGGAUAGGGAUGAGCCGUGGGGGCGGAGGAAGAUGCGCUAGUAGGGUAGAAAGUGUUGGAGAGGGGGACAAUGUGAUGAGGAUGGGGCUAAAGUCACAGACUGGCAGCUUGUCAUCUGAGGGUUUGAAUGCUACGAUAUGGAACCAUGUGAAGUGCUAGUAGAUGUACAUGUUAUCCCCCCACCCCAUAGUUACUACCUUUAUUCUUUGCUGAAAUAUUGCUAUAUUGCUGCCUGUGAACAUAGGAUAGUAUCUGUUAGAGUUGUUCAGGGGAAAAUAGUUAAGAUCAGACCCAGACUGUCAUGAUUAAAUAAGCUAAUGUACAAGAAAACCACUAGCCAGAGCUUCAUGUGUAGUUUAUCUCUCAAGCUCAUGGAUUUUGUGUGUAGCAACAUGCCUUGGGUCCUGGGCCUGUGCCUUCUAAUUCUGAUGCCAUGACUUCUGACUCAGGCGGACAUGUCUUGGACUCUCCUUGACACCCCGAAGCCACCACCCAGAGCUUUGGAGGAGGAAUCGGGCCAGUGGGUGAAUUAUGCCUUAACUGGGGCCACUUCUUUAGACAUUUGCAGAAGGAGGAACUCAGUCUCUUUUUAAAAAGAAAAAUAUGUACUUCUCUUUUCUCUUGCAGUUUCCCCAGCAUUAUUCAGAGGCAGAGUGACAGAUGUAAGGAGAGGGAUCUAAAACAUCUUUAAUAUACAACAUGAAUAUCUGAAUGGACAUUGAGAAACUGGAGAUUUCUAGUCCUGCUGAGGCAAAACCCAGAUGACCUAGAGAUGACAUAAAAGUCAGUCAUUUCUACCUGUCCCAUUACCGGUGAUGGUAAUGUUUGUCACUCAAUUAAGGCAGUAGCUCUUCUUUAGACAUUCAGCAAACAUUUGUUGAAUACCUGCAUGGGACUCUGAGUCUUGGUGUUCGAAGAGGGAAAAUGGAAAUACUCGGCCCUACAUUGCCUAAGCCCCUCACUAGGGAGAGCUGUAAGCUCUUGGGAAGGGCUUGCCACGGGGCUUUCUGUUUGUUGAGGUUCACCCUGUAUCCAGUGGCUCUUCUAGCACAGGCAGAGACAUGCCCUUUGCCGUGUGACAUUCGAGGAGACGACCAGUUUUUUUCCCUACUGACCUAUGAUCCCCACAUCCCAGCUUCUCUGCCUACUGGUUGGUCUUCCUGACAUUAGUUUUGUUCUUGUGUAUUUGAUCCAUGCACACAUUUUUACCACACCGGAUAUCCUGAAGUUGGGCUGGUUGGGGUUUUGGGAGAGGCAUGUCUAGGGUUGGUUCACUCUGUGGAUUAGGAUCUAGUUUUAUCAAGGUGGUGGGAGAAAGGCCUCACCAGGCAGCAAUCACCAAUGGAUCCCAAAUUCCCAGCUGGGCCUGCAUCCAACACAACCAACCAGGGUUUUCAGACAACUCAGAUUUUAAAAAGAAAAGCAGCAACCUGUCAGUUUGGUGACCUAGCAGAUACAUCUCAAUGCUUUUUACUUUUUAAUUGACUUUUUAAAAAUGGUGAAUUAAUGCCAUUUUCCGUAUGAAUGCAUCAUUGUGUAGAUUUGUGUAGAUGCCUUGGAGACGUCCCCUGAGAUUGAGAGCGUGGGGUGGGCAUGUUCGGGGGCGGGGAGGGAUAUGUAGAGCAACUAGAAGGAUUGAGGUUUUCCUUGCGUGCACACCCUCCUCCUGGCAGCGUGCAGUGGUGAGUUCCUGGUUCAUUGGGAGUGAAAUGGGCACCCUCCUGCUUCUGUGUGCAUACUGUAUGAGGUAUGUAGCUUUGCCAGAUCUUAGUGUGACACACCAGGAUGACAGCUAGCAAGGUCACGUCUCUGAGGGUUGUUAGGCCCCAGCCCUGGUAUAAUGCCUCUGCAAGGCAUGUUGGUCCCCUACAGUGGGCCGGCUGUGUCCAGGGAGCAGGCUGGGCUCAGAGGUAGUGCGAGCUCUCAGCUGGCCUCAGGGCCCAGCCAAGGCCCCUCAUCAUCUCUGACUAUAGGGACAGGUGGGUGCAGGGAAGGGGUGGCAAACUUAGUAACGUUGAUCUCCUUGAUAGUUUCUACCCCUGAAUGCACCUCCACACAAAAUUGUGCAGGCCUUCCCAGGGACCCUAGCCUACGGGGAAUCUCGGGGCAAGGAGAGGUGCAGGUGCUCUGGGCAGUACCACAGGUGUCCCUGUACCCUCAGGUCAUCAGGCCCAAAUACAGUGAGGAGCCAGCCACUCAGAGCCACUUGAGGGGCUCCAAAUGCCCCAUUUUCUCAUGCCCCAGGGCCUUUGAACAAACCAUUCCUUCUGCUUGCAUGCCUCUUCCAGGCUCAGCUGAAUUGCAUGAUACAGUGACAGUGGAAGGAGUGGAGGAGGAUCCAACAUCACAGAUACUUUAACAGUGAAUAUGUUAAAUCUAAUACAUCAUAAGAGAGUCCCGGGUGUGAAGGAAGAGUGCUCCUUGCUGCUGGUGCUGUCCCAUCUGCUCCCUGCGGGGCCCCUUGCAGCCCGUGAGCUUGACUUGGCCUUGGCUGAGUCAGCAGGGGUGGUGGGCAGGAGACCCCUGGCUGCACAGGGAGGGCCAGCAGUGUGCUGUCUGCUUAAACUGUAAGUAAAAGAAGUGAGGAUGGUCCAGGCGCAGUGGCUCACGCCUGUAAUCCCAGCACUUUGGGAGGCCAAGGCGGGUGGAUCAUGAGGUCAGGAGAUCGAGACCAUCCUGGCUAACACGGUGAAACCCCGUCUCUACUAAAAAUACAAAAAAUUAGCCGGGCGUGGUGGCAGGUGCCUGUAGUCCCAGCUACUCGGGAGGCUGAGGCAGGAGAAUGGCGUGAACCCGGGGGGUGGAGCUUGCAGUGAGCCAAGAUUGCGCCACUGCACUCCAGCCUGGGCGACAGAAUGAGACUCCAUCUCAAAAAAAAAAAAAAAGAAGUGAGGAUGACAGGAGAAGGUAGAUGGUGCAACAUGAGGGUGCUUUCUACCAACAAGGUGUGCAGCAUUGGACACGCAUGACCACGUGACCUGCAGCUCUGAUGGUGCAACAUGAGGGUAUGUCCUACCAACAAGGUGUGCAGCAUUGGACAUACUUGACCACGUGACCUGCGGCUCUGAAGGUCCCACCUGUUCUCGUUCUAAAGUCACCAUUUCUGACCGCUGUGCUGUGGAAGGGGAGGCAAUUAACCAGAUGAGGCGUCCCAACAGAUUCUCCUAUCGAUUGUGAAAAGUGGGUCCACUUCAGCUUACAGAUGAGGUCAUCAUGCCCAGGCUCCAAGGCCACCACACAAGUGAAGGCAAGAGCACUGAGGACAUUUCAACCUAGAUCUGGCUAGUUUCCAAACUAAUUCUGCUGCCUCAAUUAGCAAUUCACAUCAAACCUCCUACGUUUUGAUUAAAUGUUAUUUGAAACUCUUGAUAUUAAACCCAAGAUUCCACAGUCUAGGUGUCCAAAACUAAUUUGACUUCCUGUUUCAAGGGCACCUACUUUUUCUCUCCUUGCAAACUUGAGCACAGUGAAGAUGAGCAUUUCUGGACCUGAAGGAGCAUUUGGGGAACAGUUCCAUGGAGGGAGAUGCUUGCUGGAGCAGUAUUUUGUGGAUUCAUUUCGGCUUGUCUGUGGCAGCCGAACAGCGGUUUCCAACAAAGGCUUUCACUGACUCAGCUCCAAGCAUGACUCGUAAAUCUCCUUUUCCCCUCUUGCUGAUUUUUCUAGGCAUCUAUUGUCCACACCCUGACCACACACUGUCACCCAUCAGAGUCCCCAGUUGACUCAGGUUUACACUGUGCCAUCCGAACUCUUGAUAGAGAGUCCCCCUAAAAGGAACCUGAGGUGAUUGCAACAUAAAUGUCAAAGGUUGCAAGAAUAAUAUGUUGUGUUAGGAUGGCCCUUCCAUCCAGAUAUCAUGGCCGUUUCUAUCUUGAGAAUUAUUUGCUGACCAAACGAUGUUACGGUACAUUUACUUAAUAACAAAUUUUUCAACUUUCUUCAUCCAUUCCUUCACUGCAUAUGUCACCCUCUCUCUGAAUAAUGAAUCAUCAGAUUCUUGGAAAAAGGAAAUCAUGAAGGAGGAACCAUGGUUGUAACAGGCAGAUAAAGCUUCAGCUUGGUUUUUUAGACACUCAUGGUAGCGUUUGCGUAUGGUCACGACGCUCAUGAGAGUCUUGUCUUGGUUUCUUCUAGCCAUCUGGCUCUAUGAGGCUCCAGCAAGCACUGUGAGACCCGGCUCCUUGGGACAAGGCUGGAGAGGGCUAGUGUUAGGAUUGGAUCUGUCCGCCUUGCCGUUUCCAGGUCAGAGAAUGUGCCAGAAUGCGAUGAGAACUCCCUAGUUGGAGGGGAAUUGGGAUUGCAGGAGCUGCCGGCUCUCAGGCUUUCACUGUCCAUCUCCUUUAGAAAUUUAUUUUUUAUUUUAUUUAUUUAUUUUUGAGACAGAGUCUCGCUCUGUCGCCCAGGCUGGAAUGCAGUGGCGUGAUCUCAGCUCGUUGCGGCCUUUGGCUCAGGUUCGAGUAAUUCUCCUGCCUCAGCCUCUUGAGUAGCUGGGAUUACAGGCGUGCACCAACACACCCGGCUAAUUUUUUGUAUUUUCAGUAGAGACAGGGUUUCACCAUGUUGGCCAGCUGGUCUAGAACUCCUGACCUCAAGUGAUCCUCCCACCUCAGCCUCCCAAAGUGCUGGGAUUACAGGCAUGAGCCACUGUGCUUGGCCUUAGAAAUUUAUCUUUUCUCACUGAAUGAAUCAUUGCAACACCAAAAGCCAUUCCCUGGAGAGGAAGAAUCACAAUAUGGAAGUUAUUUCCUAGCUUCCCCAAAUGACAAAGGAAGAUAAGUGAGCGUCGCAGUUCAUCAGCAACUGUUGCUCAAAGGCUUUUUAUUCCUUAACAUAAUGAGGAAAAAUCAUUACCAAGCUCCCAUGUGUGAGAUACAGACGUUAAUCCAAAACGACAUGAGGUCCCCUCACCAGGGACUGGCUGGGAGGACAGAAGGUACACACUCUGUCAGCAAUAAAUAAACCCCCAUCAAUUGGGGAGAUGUGUGUGCUCGGUUUUGCCUUUUAUGAUUCCAACUUGUUCUUGUUUUCUGUAUUUUUUUCUUUUGAUUAAAUUCUACCAGGCUUGGUUGGUAUGGUGGGGAAGAGUGUUAGGAUUUUCCAGCUAACUUGGGACCUGUAAUUCAAACCAGUUCUCAGCCAAUUUCAAUACAUCAUGAUUUUAUGUUUGUGAAAACAUAGGCCUUGCAACACAACAGGCUUGGGGUAGUCAUUUCAGGGAAAAUUCAUGAUGAUACAAAGUGACCCACUGGGCCUAUAAAGACUUUACAAAAAAUUCUAAAUUAAAAGACACUGAAGAGGAAAGUUUAGUCAUGAUUCCAGUGAUUCUUUAACAUGGUUUGGCAAACUGCUGUCUGGGGACCAAAUCUGGCCCACAACCUGUUUUCGUAAAUAAAGUUUUAUUGAAACACAGCCAUGCCCACUCAUUUACAUGUUGUCUAUGGCUGCAUUGCACUAUAAUGGCAGAGUUGAGUGGUUGCAACAAAGACUGGAUGCUCUGCACCUAAAAUAGUUACCAGGUGGCCCUUUGGAGAAAAGGGUUGCUACCUCCUGCAUGAGUGGAGUAACAUGCCUUUCCGUGCGUGCUGCAUGAGGCCCUCUCUGGAGACCUGGGUGAGCUGCUAGUCCCUGGGGGAGACUGUCACUUGUAUGACUCAUUAGUCUUCUGUCUCACUGCUGACGCACUUGGGACCCAGGGCGGAUAUGCCGUGACAAAAUAAUCCUGCUGCCAUUUCCAGGUCCCCAUUUGCCAGGGGCCAGAAUUCUAAUCAGUUGUGUAGUAGGUGGCUGUGAGAAAGAAUGUUCUAAAGCCUUUGGGGCAGAAAUUUCACCUGGGUGUGUGAAUGUCAUUUGCAGGCUUCACUUUUGUCCUUUGCUUCAGUUAGAGUCAACAGAUUUUUUGAGGGUCUGCUGUGUGAAGGAAAACCCCAGUCAUUUCACCUGAUAGUCAUUCCAUUCCCUUCUCUCCUUCCUCACAACCUCACAAUGGCCGGUUGCUUUCCUGUUUAGUUAUGAGCGGCUCAGGGUCAGUGAUAACCAGGUCCAUGCAUGUUUGUGUCUCUCCACAAGGUCAGACUUUUAUUGACGUGAUUUCAAUCACAAAAGCUGGAAGCUCCAUUGAGUUCCCAAGGAGGAACUUCCCCUUACUACUUCCCAUUCACUUAGGAGUCAGAGCCGCGGGCACACAGGCUCAAGCCACUCCACAGGUCAGUCAGUGUUGCAAACCAUGCAUAAUAGUACACUUAUCAAUAAAUAAAUGAUUAAACAUUUCACAAUAAAUGAAGUAACAUUUAACAUCAAAAGAAAAGGGUUAAUGGACCAGUCCAGGGAGAGCAACAUGAAAAAAAAAAGAAUGUCCUGGCCUGGUCUGGGCAGUCCAUUGGUCUCACAAGGAAGAGUCUUUGAUGUGGGCAGAGCAUUGGGCAGUGGAUGCUGGGUGCUGAUCACAAGCGACAGCAAGAUGGAGUCUGUGGGGACAGCCAUUUCUAGCUGGUGAAGUACUGCUCUUAUGGCCGCAGAGUCCUCUGGUGAGGACUGAGUGGAGGAAUGUACUUGGUUAUGUCCUUGUUGGAAGCAGUCUUCAUUGAUUAGGCAAAACAUCCAGUCUUGUUGGCAAGGUGCCUUUUAAAAUGUAAGAUGGAGUCUUUCUCUAAGAUGGAGUUUACUGUGUCAAGGGUACUGUAUACAGUUAUCACUAGCUAGUCCAGUAUUCUAGACAGCGUAUGUGUGUCUGUCUGUCCAUCAUGCGUACACACACACACAUACACAUUUUCAACACUGGUAGAAGGGAAUGAUUAUCCUGUUUCUCCCAAAGACACUUGUUGGGCUUAAGUACCAGUUUCUACUGUGAGCCCUUUAAUUCAUGAUCAUUAGUGAUAGUGUGAUUAAAAUUCUGCAGCUACAAUUUUGUGAUGACUUAUUUGUGCCGGGGACUGUGCUGGGGGCUUCCCUUGGACUCUCUUAUGCUGUCUCACAGCCAAACAGUGAGAAAAGCUCUUCUGUUCUCUCACUUUGCAGUUGGGGAGCUAGGGCUGGGAGCAUCACACUUGUCCAAGGUUAUACAGAGAUACUGAAGGGCAAAGCCUGGGUCGGUCUCAGUUUGGGUCGCCUGACCCCAGGCCACCACUGCCUUUCUCCCUUUCACAGAUGUGGAUGCUGGACCCAGGAACUCUGACACCCAGUGUGCCCCAGUAGCUCUGCCUGCCAGCAGCAGGGGUGGCUGUCUGCCAAUUCCCUUAGGAGUUCCAGCCCUCCUCCCCGCCCCUCCACACUCAGUGCUCCACUGGCCUUGCUUGAUUAGAUUCCCCAGCUGGUCUGUUUACUGGGCCUGGCAGAGCUCCUUACCCCCAUGCCCCCACUCAGUGGUCCUCACAGUCCUGUUUGCAGCAGCCACAGGUAGUCCCUAGGGGUGGGGCAGACUCAGGCUUCAGCUGGAGCCCCUGCCUGCGGGUGCCUCUUGGCUGUAAGGCACUCUUCCUACCAAUAUGGCCUUUUCUGUCUCUGUUUAGGAGCCCCUCUCUGAAACCUUAGGUCUGUGUGACCCCAGAGUCCAUUUCUGUUUCACCCCUGGUGACCUCCUUACUGUGCAGAGAAUGUGUUCGUUGAAAUUCAAAGUAGAUAAGAAAGGCUGAAGCUCAGUGUCACCUCCCUUAGCAGGGGCUCAGUGGCCACAGUGUGAACAGAAGGGGUAGGACAGUUAGGUGGGGCAGGUGUGCAAUGAAUGGAACUCACCUAGAGCUUUCUGUGCCCCAGGCAUCAUGCUGGGUCCUUUAUUGCACACAUACCUGUGACCUGCUUCCUGUUUGCACCUUGCACAAUUGCUGCCUGGUGGGUGUUAGCUGCAUUGUGUUAGGAAUGAGGGGAACGGGCUCAUGAGGUUUAAGGGGCCUACUCAAGAUCAUAGAGCAAGUAGGUUGGAAUGGAGAUUUAAAUCAGACUGACUCUGAAGUCGGAAACCCCCUAUUCUGAGCAGCAGUGGCUGGAGAAAGGCCUCCUGAGUCAGUGCCAGGAGGCAGAGCCCAGGGUCUGCUCUGUCCCCAAGCCUGUGUCUGUGGGCAGGCCACUUAGCCUUGCUGGGGGGUGGUGCUGCCUGAUUUAUGAGUGGAGGAUAACUAUAGCCAGCCCAUUCCACCCACAGAACUGAUGGAGACAAAAUGAGAUUAUGUUUUUUCAGAACUUGGCAGCUGCCAGGGGUUGGUGAGGGACCCAUUGGGCCUUCCUGAAGAGCCCUGGCUGCCAGUGCUGUCUGAGUGGAUUUUCCCUCUAGUCAGUAGCUCCUGCACAUGCAGAAGUUUUUGUUUUAAUUUUAGUCACCAGGAUAUAACUGUCCCUUCAAAUGUACUUUGUAAGCACUAUUACCUUGGAGCCACCACGAUCAUGGGGAGGUUUGUGGGAGUGAAUGUCAGGUAGUGGCACAGGAAUUCAGAUGGGGGUUUGGCCCUGGCUUUGUCCUUCCUUUCCUCCCUCCCUCCCUUCCUCCCUUCCUUUUCUUCUUCAUUCCUCAUGCAUUUAUUGAGCACCUAAUAUGGGUAAGGAGCUUGUAUUAGUCCAUUCUCAUGCUGCUAUAAAGGACUGCCUGAGACUGGGUACUUUAUAAAGAAAAGAGGUUUAAUUGAUCCACAGUUCACAUGGCUGAGGAGGCCGCAGGAAACUUACAAUCAUGGCGGAAGGGGAAGCAAACACGUCCUUCUUCACAUGAUGGCAGGAAGGAGAAUUGCUGAGCAAAAUGGGGAAAAGCCCCUUAUAAAACCAUCAGAUCUCAUGAGCACCCACUCCUAUCAUGAGAAUAGCAUGAGGGUAACUGCCCCCAUGAUUCAAUUACCUCCCACCUGGUCCCUCCCAGGACACAUGGGGAUUAUGGGAACUAAAUUCAAGAUGAGAUUUCAGUGGGGACACAGCCAAACCAUAUCAUAGCUGGGCGAGCCAUCGUGAAAUGGGUGAAGAUGCAAUUUGCCUAAUCCUUGCCAUCAAAGUAGAGAACCUGUUUUUGAGUGUCUGCUGCAGGCCAGACUUUGCAAACUUAAGUUCAUUUAAGUUUCACCGCUGUCCUCUGAGAUAGGUGUCUGUCACUCAUGUUCAAAACCUCCAGUGCCUUCCCGUCUCACAUAAAGCAAAAGCCACAAUGCCCCUCUGCCCCUGGCUCCACCUCCCCCUCACCAAAGCAAUCACCGGGCUGGCCUCUGGGCUGUUCCUCGCUUUCCUUGCUGUCUGGGGGAGGCACCCUCACUGCUCACUCCCACACUCCCUUCAGGUCACAGCUCACAUAGCAUCUCAUCAAGGAGGUCUUCCAAGACUCCCUAAAACAUCAGAACAAGACUCCCCGAACCCCGUCCCACCCAGGAUUCACCUUUUCCUGCACUGCAGUGAUAACCAAAGAACAGGCUCUGUGUUUACUUAUUUGCUUGCCUGCAGUUUUCCCCAACUCCCCUGACACAUGCAUCCCCCGCCUCAUGUAAGCACCAUGAGAGUAGCGGCUUUGCUCACAGUGGGUUCCCCCUUGCCCAGGCACUCAGGGAGUAUCUGUUGAAUCACUGUAUAUCACAUGCAGUUGGCACAUUUGUGCUUUGGCAUAUACAUUCUCCUGCCUCAUCACAGAGCCCAAGAGGAGAGGCAAAUAGAAGGAGAUAGUACACACGGUGCAUGGAUCAGAGACCUGCACAUUGUUAGUUUUCCUAAAAUUGAUCCCCAAAUUCAAUUCAUUCUCAAUCAAAAUCGCAUCAAGCUAUCACUUUUUUUUUUUGAGGCACAGGGUUUCACUCUGUUGUUUAGGCUGGUGCUCACUGUAACCUUGAACUCCGGGCUCAAGCAGUGUUCUUGCCUCAUCCUCCCAAGUAGCUAGGACCACAGGUAUGCACCACCAUGACAAGCUAAUUUUUACUUUUUUGUAGAGACGGAAUCUUGCUGUGUUGCCCAGACGACUCGUGGCCUCAGGCAAUCCUCAUGCCCCAACCUCCCAAAGCAAUGAUAUUAUGGGCAUGAGCCACUGCACCCAGCUGCAUCAGGCAUUUCUAUAGAAAUUGACAAGCUAAUUCUAAAAUUUAUGUGGCUGUGCAACGACUUAGAAUGGCCAAGGUAAACUUGAAUAAGAACAACGUUGGAAGGCCCACCCUACAUUUAUGUCAGUAAUUACUGCACAACUUUAGGAGUUAAGAUAGUGUGGUACCGGCAUAACAAUAGACAAAGGGUGUGGUGGAAUUGGGAAACAUGGAGUUAGUUUGUUUAAACAACAGAGGAGUUAUAUUUUCAAGUGAAAUGCUCAAUAUAUUUCCAGAUGAAGGGCCUCUAAAUGUAAAGCAAUGGCUCCAAUUGUUAAUCUGAUACAGGUUCACUCAUUAUAUAUCUAAGUCCAAAAGUACAGGCAAAAAUCAUAUAAUUUUUUUCAGCGUAAUAAUUGGAUCUACCACUUUAAAUUUAGAUGUCUUUCACCUAAAAAAAAAAAAAAACAAACCUGAAAGUUGAAGGAAAACACAUUGUGCAUAUUACAUGUAAAUGUAACUAACAUACCUCUUAUGAGUGAGUUUAUCGCCACUUCAGUCGGGUGGCCAAGGCUGGCAUCCACAGUGACAAGCCAUGUUGACAGCAUGAUGUGAUAAGAAGGACACUUUAUUUCCUGGGUCUUCCUCUCAAAAACCCGUAUUCUGAGCCUGACUUUGAGAAAAACAUCAGACAAACCCGAACUGAAGAACAUUCUACAGAUACUCCUCAAAAUUGUCAAGGCCUGAGAAACUCGCAGAGCCAAGGGGUGUCUAAGGAGAUGUGCUGACAAAGCGUGCUGGGGUGUCCUGGAUAGAGUGCUAGAGUGGAAAACGGACGUUACGUAAAAACUGAGGAAGUCUGAGCAAGUUUGUCUGAAAAUUAUGGACUUCUUUUUUUUUUUUUUUUUUGAGACAGAGUCUGGCUCUGUCGCCCAAGCUGGAGUGCAGUGGCGUGAUCACGGUGCACUGCAACCUCUGCCUCUCAGGCUCAAGCGAUUCUCCUGCCUCACCCUCCCAAGUAGCUGGGAUUACAGGUGUGUACCAUCACAUGGGCUAAUUUUUGUAUUUUUAGUAGAGAUGGGGUUUCACCGUGUUUCCCAGGCUGGUCUCGAACUCCUGACCUCAGCUGAUCCACCUACCUUGGCUUCCCAAAGUGCUGGGAUUACAGGUGUGAGCCACUGGCACCUGGCCUGGACUUUUCUUAAUAAGAAGGUAUCAGUGUUGCGACAAAUGCACCAUACUAAUGUAAAAUGUUAAUAACAGGAAACUGGGUGUGGGGAUAAGGGAACUUUCUCUACUCUCUUUGCAUUUUCUGUAAAUCUAAAGUUGUUCUUAAAAAUGCGGUUUAUUUUUUAAUAAGUUUAUCUUAUGUGUCUUUCACCCCACAGACAUCCUGAUUCUGUCCUGCAGAAUUGAGACACAUAGGAUAAAUGAAGCUAAAUAUAGUCCAUAAAUAAUGCAUAUAAGAUCACACACUAUUUGAUGAAAGUGCUAAUGCAAUUCAACAGGGAAAUAAAUGCCUUUUAAACAAACUAUUCUGGAGGGAUGUCCAUAUUGGGGGCGUGGUGGGGGUGGUGGUGAAUAAUGUCCGAGCCCUAUCCAACACUACACAUAAAAUUUAAGUUGCAAUGGACUGUGGAUCAAAAUGUGAAAGCUAAGUGAUGAAGCUUCUAGAGGAAAACAUAGGAUAAUUCUUCACGACAUUGAGGUGGCAAAUAUAUUUUAGAAUACAAAAAUCGCUAACCAUAAAAUAAAAGGUUGAUAAAUUAGACUUUAUCAAAAUUUAAAACUGCUCAUCAGAAGACACCAUCCAAAAAGCACCAAGGCCACCCACAGACUGGGAGAAAAUGUUCACCAUUCAUAUUUUCUGACAAAGUACUUGUACCUGGUAGAGAUAAACUUCUAUGAUCAGUAUGAUGAAGACUAACAGUCCAAUUUUUUUAAGCAGGCAAAAGAAUUAGACAUCUUACAAAAGAAGAUAUCUAAAUAGCCAGUGAAAAGUGCUCUGCAUCAUUAGUCAUCAGGGAAAUGCAAAUCCCAAUGAGAUAUCAUAACACACCCACGUAAAUUACUAAAAUUAAGAAAUAUUACAUGUUAGAAUGGAGCCACUGGAACUCCUUGUACACUACUGGUGCAAAUAUGAAAUUGUACGUUCACUUUGGAAAACAGCCUGGCAGUUUUUAAUAAAGUAAGCAUACAGCUACCCCGUGUUCCAAGAAUGACACUCCUAGAUAUAUACACCCAAGAGGAACGAGUGCUUAUUUCCACAGAGACUUCUAUAUGACUCAACACUGGUGAUGUUAAUGUUGACCAGUAGGUGAAAGUGGUGUCUGCCAACCUUCUUCCCUGUAAAAUGUUUUUCUUUUGUAAUUAAUAAAUACCUUGAGAGAGAUACUUUGAAACUCUGCAAAUAUCCUGUUUCUCCCCAAGCUUUUUCACAUUAAUUUUAGCAUCCAUCGGUGGAUCUUGCCUGCAACAAUGAUUACUAUGGUAUGCCGAUGGUGAUUUUCUUUUCUUUUCUUUUCCCCUCCCCUCCCCUCCCUUCUCCUCUUCUCUUCUCUUCUUUUUCCUUUUUGUGGAGAACAGUGCCUCACUAUAUUCCCCAGGCAGGUCUCAAACUCCUGGGUUCAAGCUAUCCUUCCCACUCUCCCACCCUAAGGGCUGGGAUUACAGGCAUGAAGCAUGAAGCAUGAUGGUGAUUUUCUAUUGCCAUUGUUCCUUCUACAUUUAUUAAUUGGAAUCUUCUGUAAGAGGAAGCUGUCUCCCUCCCUCCUUCUACCUCCCCAUUUGUUUAUUUAUCUGGGGGCUCUUUGUAAAGGUGUGGGUGGAGAGUAGGGAACCAAGAGGGACAGUGUGGUUACCUGAGGUGGGGAACGAUAAAACAAAUAAAUAAGACUCAUGAGUAUUUAGUUUGUGGCACAGGCUAUAAUCAAUACGGUUGUCACUCAUUUUGUUGCUCAGGUUGUUCUGGGAACCCCUCUCAGCCUCUCCUUUCAUCAGGCUCCCAUAAUUAUUGUUACUGUUGAUCAUGAUUUCUUGUGUGGUCAGUUGCUAGGUGCAGAUGCCUGGAUUUCAAACUGGGGGGGAUGUUACAAAGCUUAAAAAGACUCCGGAGAGUUUGUGUUCUAGGAAAACCCAAGAAACCCAGAACUGGAAGAGCCCCAGAGAGAUGAAUGUUACCGGGCGUGUUCCCUUCUCUCUUCCCUGACGCUCCCCUGUGCAGAGGAUCCUGCAGACAUGGCUAAAGGAGAUGCAGCAGGAGAUCAGAGGGAAAAACUGCAUAGAAAAUCUAAUGGAUGAAGAUGAGAAAGACAGAGCCAAGAGAGCUUCUCGAAACAAGUCUGAGAAGAAGCGUCGGGACCAGUUCAAUGUUCUCAUCAAAGAGCUCAGUUCCAUGCUCCCUGGCAACACGCGGAAAAUGGACAAAACCACCGUGUUGGAAAAGGUCAUCGGAUUUUUGCAGAAACACAAUGAAGUCUCAGCGCAAACGGAAAUCUGUGACAUUCAGCAAGACUGGAAGCCUUCAUUCCUCAGUAAUGAAGAAUUCACCCAGCUGAUGUUGGAGGCAUUAGAUGGCUUCAUUAUCGCAGUGACAACAGACGGCAGCAUCAUCUAUGUCUCUGACAGUAUCACGCCUCUCCUUGGGCAUUUACCGUCGGAUGUCAUGGAUCAGAAUUUGUUAAAUUUCCUCCCAGAACAAGAACAUUCAGAAGUUUAUAAAAUCCUUUCUUCCCAUAUGCUUGUGACGGAUUCCCCCUCCCCAGAAUACUUAAAAUCUGACAGCGAUUUAGAGUUUUAUUGCCAUCUUCUCAGAGGCAGCUUGAACCCAAAGGAAUUUCCAACUUAUGAAUACAUAAAAUUUGUAGGAAAUUUUCGCUCUUACAACAAUGUGCCUAGCCCCUCCUGUAAUGGUUUUGACAACACCCUUUCAAGACCUUGCCGGGUGCCACUAGGAAAGGAGGUUUGCUUCAUUGCCACCGUUCGUCUGGCAACACCACAAUUCUUAAAGGAAAUGUGCAUAGUUGACGAACCUUUAGAGGAAUUCACUUCAAGGCAUAGCUUGGAAUGGAAAUUUUUAUUUCUGGAUCACAGAGCACCUCCAAUCAUAGGAUACCUGCCUUUUGAAGUGCUGGGAACCUCAGGCUAUGACUACUACCACAUUGAUGACCUGGAGCUCCUGGCCAGGUGUCACCAGCACCUGAUGCAGUUUGGCAAAGGGAAGUCGUGUUGCUACCGGUUUCUGACCAAAGGUCAGCAGUGGAUCUGGCUGCAGACUCACUACUACAUCACCUACCAUCAGUGGAACUCCAAGCCCGAGUUCAUCGUGUGCACACACUCGGUGGUCAGUUACGCAGAUGUCCGGGUGGAAAGGAGGCAGGAGCUGGCUCUGGAAGACCCGCCAUCCGAGGCCCUCCACUCCUCAGCACUAAAGGACAAGGGCUCAAGCCUGGAACCUCGGCAGCACUUUAACACACUCGACGUGGGUGCCUCGGGCCUUAAUACCAGUCAUUCGCCAUCGGCGUCCUCAAGAAGUUCCCACAAAUCCUCGCACACAGCCAUGUCAGAACCCACCUCCACUCCCACCAAGCUGAUGGCAGAGGCCAGCACCCCGGCUUUGCCAAGAUCAGCCACCCUGCCCCAAGAGUUACCUGUCCCCGGGCUCAGCCAGGCAGCCACCAUGCCGGCCCCUCUGCCUUCCCCAUCGUCCUGCGACCUCACACAGCAGCUCCUGCCUCAGACCGUUCUGCAGAGCACGCCCGCUCCCAUGGCACAGUUUUCGGCACAGUUCAGCAUGUUCCAGACCAUCAAAGACCAGCUAGAGCAGCGGACGCGGAUCCUGCAGGCCAAUAUCCGGUGGCAACAGGAAGAGCUCCACAAGAUCCAGGAGCAGCUCUGCCUGGUCCAGGACUCCAACGUCCAGAUGUUCCUGCAGCAGCCAGCUGUAUCCCUGAGCUUCAGCAGCACCCAGCGACCUGAGGCUCAGCAGCAGCUACAGCAAAGGUCAGCUGCAGUGACUCAGCCCCAGCUCGGGGCGGGCCCCCAACUUCCAGGGCAGAUCUCCUCUGCCCAGGUCACAAGCCAGCACCUGCUCAGAGAAUCAAGUGUGAUAUCAACCCAGGGUCCAAAGCCAAUGAGAAGCUCACAGCUAAUGCAGAGCAGCGGCCGCUCUGGAAGCAGCCUAGUGUCCCCGUUCAGCAGCGCCACAGCUGCGCUCCCGCCAAGUCUGAAUCUGACCACACCUGCUUCCACCUCCCAGGAUGCCAGCCAGUGCCAGCCCAGCCCAGACUUCAGCCAUGAUCGGCAGCUCAGGCUGUUGCUGAGCCAGCCCAUCCAGCCCAUGAUGCCCGGGUCCUGUGACGCAAGGCAGCCCUCGGAAGUCAGCAGGACGGGACGGCAAGUCAAGUACGCCCAGAGCCAGACCGUGUUUCAAAAUCCAGACGCACACCCCGCCAACAGCAGCAGCGCCCCGAUGCCCGUCCUGCUGAUGGGGCAGGCGGUGCUCCACCCCAGCUUCCCUGCCUCCCAACCAUCGCCCCUGCAGCCUGCACAGGCCCGGCAGCAGCCACCGCAGCACUACCUGCAGGUACAGGCACCAACCUCUUUGCACAGUGAGCAGCAGGACUCGCUACUUCUCUCCACCUACUCACAACAGCCAGGGACCCUGGGCUACCCCCAACCACCCCCAGCACAGCCCCAGCCCCUACGUCCUCCCCGAAGGGUCAGCAGUCUGUCUGAGUCGUCAGGCCUCCAGCAGCCGCCCCGAUAAUGCCCCGGCACUGAAGUCGGGACACAAUCAGCUUUAACCAAUGGAUGAGGGGGGUGGCCACAGGAGAUGGGGAGAGGAGUCUGAACUAAACCCCUGGCUUUUGUGCACACUGCAUACGUUUCAGAACUCCUGGAUGGUAACCAUCUCUGGAGUGCAGCGCUUGCUGCAGUGGAAAUGAUCAGGAAUACUGACCGUGUUUCUCUUGCCUCCGAGGUUCUUGGGCACACUCUAUAGCCAUACUGGACAGGAACCAGGUGCCCCGUGUAGGCAUCGUCGGUCGGUUUGCCGUCAGAGAUGGCGCAUCUCGCUGCAUCCCCCGAGAGUACACCGGUUGCUCUAGCCACCUGCGGCCCGCCCAUCUGCGCUAGCUGGCCUUCACGCUCUUGAUCGUCUUUCCUUUGUAUUGGAGAAGGACUGGGUCAGAGAUCUGUUGGAGAGAGAGAAUAAAGAGAUUAUUUUUCAUUAUUUUUAAAUGGUUGUUUUUGUUUUAAUUUGCACAGCUACACAGAGGAAAUAACUUAGGCACUUUCUGUUUUUUUUAAAAAAAUAAUAAGGUCUCAUGGCUUCAUUUAGAGACCACAGUAACAACAGCAGCCCACCAAUCAGAGAAGCUGGUUGUUAUUAACCAAGCUACAGAUUCACACUUUCUGGCCUAAACCCUAAUGGGAUGAGGCUUUUCACCCCAGGCCAUGCUGGUGGUGAUUUUUUAGCCCCUAAAUAAAACACUGGACUAUUUCCUGUUUACUUCAUUGAUUGCAACUACAAAGGUGGACUCAAAGCAAAGCACAAUCAUGCCAGCCAACAUUCCAGAAUUCUGCUGAGAACUCCAAGUCUGUGAGGGGAGAGGUUUUACAAGCCAGACAGGCCUGGGGGACUGCAGUCCCCAAGGAGACCCUGCCACAUGCUGGCCCUUUGAGUGAGAAUGCUGCAUCUUUCUACAUAUCUUCAUGAGAAUACUGAGAAUUGGAUUUUCCUUUUCAAAAUGCACUUUGCUUUUUUUGUAUGUUUUGUUAUGUUGAGAUGUUUCUAAAGAAAAGAUUUUAUGUAAUUAUAAGAUGAAGCGUAGUGAAUUGUACAGCUGUUGUAAUAAUGACCUAUUUCUAUAUAAAAUAAAAUUGUAUGGCUUAUGUGUAAAUUAUUUUGUAUCUGAGAUACCAGUUCCUUUUCCCAAAUAUAAAAGUAUAAAAGUUUUCUUGUGUUUUUCUGUGAGUGAAAAUUUUGUAAUAAAUUAACAAAUUUGUACAAUU